AGUAGCUCUCGCCUGCGGGUGGUUUGACAAGGCUGGCGGCGCCACACCAGCGACCAGGUGAGGCCGACCAGGCACAAAGGGGUGGGGGGCCUGGAGGGCCGAGUUGAUGUUGGGGUGCUUCAUUCUAGGUCCCAGAGCUUCUCUGAGGGAACUGGCCCUGGGUUUUGCGCGGGAUGUCGUGGGACCCCUCUCCAGCAGAUCCUCCCCAAAGCUUGGGAGAGGUUCAUGCAGCCUCUUUAGACCCGGAGCCGCAGCCUGGAGCCCGCGGGUGUCUGGGGGUCUUCCUGGGCCUCAGCUGUCUAAGGUCCUGAAGCCCUAUCCUCGAGGCCCAGCCCGCCCCACGCAGCCCCCGCCCCACCCCGGGCCACCUCCAUGCCCGCAUAUGCAUGAGAGAGGUGAUGCCAUGAGCUGUCCUGACCUCUCUUUUGUCUCACACCUCUCUAAGCCCCAGGGCCCGCAGUAAUCCCAACUCCACUCUCAACCUCUACUGAGGACUGGGGACGGGAGUAGAUGACUCAGCCCCGAGCAGGAAUGAGGGGUGAAAGGUUCCCACCUGCCUUGUAUAAAGUCAGCGAGAGUCCAAGAUGGUGCCUGGACGGGGCAGUUCUCUGGCCUAGGGCCUGGAGCUCACACUUCUGAGAGGCAUCGCAAGCGAGGGCCUUCACGUUACUGAGACCCCAGCCCCGCACAGAGGCUCAUGGAGCUCGAAGCACGCAGGGCUGGCCUCUCCAGAGCUAGCAGAUUCCUUCUGGACCUGUAGGGUGCCGCCCUAGCCCAGCCGCCAUGGCGCAGGGUUUCGCAGUGGGCUUCGACCCACUGGGCCUAGGAGACCUGAGCUCCGGCUCUCUGAGCUCCCUCUCCUCCCGAGGCCACCUAGGCAGCGACUCAGGCUCCACCGCAACGCGAUACCUGCUAAGGAAGCAACAACGGCUGCUGAACGGGCCCCCCCGCGGAAUCCGAGCCUCAUCGCCCAUGGGACGCGUCAUCCUCAUCAACUCCCCCAUCGAAGCCAACAGUGAUGAAAGUGACAUCAUCCAUUCAGUCCGGGUGGAGAAGAGUCCAGCAGGGAGGCUGGGCUUCAGCGUGCGCGGGGGCUCAGAGCAUGGCCUGGGCAUCUUCGUCAGCAAAGUGGAGGAAGGCAGCAGUGCAGAGCGGGCUGGCCUGUGCGUGGGGGACAAGAUCACGGAGGUGAAUGGGCUGAGCCUGGAGAGCACCACCAUGGGUAGCGCCGUAAAGGUGCUGACCAGCAGCAGCCGCCUGCACAUGAUGGUUCGGCGCAUGGGCCGUGUGCCGGGCAUCAAGUUCUCCAAGGAGAAGACCACGUGGGUGGAUGUGGUGAAUCGGCGCCUGGUAGUGGAGAAGUGCGGUUCAACACCCUCCGACACCAGCUCAGAAGAUGGUGUCCGGCGCAUCGUCCACCUAUACACAACCUCCGACGACUUCUGCCUGGGCUUCAACAUCCGUGGGGGCAAGGAGUUUGGCCUGGGCAUCUAUGUGUCCAAAGUGGACCAUGGUGGGCUGGCCGAGGAGAAUGGCAUCAAGGUGGGGGACCAGGUCCUGGCAGCCAACGGUGUCAGGUUUGACGACAUCAGCCACAGCCAGGCCGUGGAGGUGCUGAAGGGCCAAACGCACAUCAUGCUGACCAUCAAGGAGACCGGCCGGUAUCCUGCCUACAAGGAGAUGGUUUCUGAGUACUGCUGGCUGGACCGACUGAGCAACGGGGUGCUGCAGCAGCUGUCCCCGGCCUCUGAGAGCAGCUCCAGCGUCUCUUCGUGCGCCUCCAGCGCCCCCUACAGCUCGGGCUCCCUGCCGUCGGACCGCAUGGACAUCUGCCUCGGGCAGGAGGAGCCCGGCAGCCGCGGCCCAGGCUGGGGGCGGGCGGACACAGCCAUGCAGACGGAGCCCGAUGCGGGAGGCCGGGUGGAGACCUGGUGCAGCGUGCGGCCCACAGUCAUCCUCAGGGACACCGCCAUCCGCUCGGACGGCCCCCAUCCCGGCCGCCGCCUUGACUCUGCGCUCUCUGAGUCUCCCAAGACGGCUUUGCUGCUGGCCCUCAGCCGACCCCGGCCCCCCAUCACGCGCUCCCAGAGCUAUCUGACCUUGUGGGAGGAGAAGCAGCAGCGGAAGAAGGAGAAGUCGGGGUCCCCUGGGGAGAAGGGUGCCCUGCAGCGCUCCAAGACGCUGAUGAACCUCUUCUUCAAGGGAGGGCGGCAGGGGAGGCUAGCGCGGGACGGGCGCAGAGAGGCCUGGACACUGGACAGCGGGAGCCUGGCCAAAACUUACCCUCGCCUGGACAUAGAGAAAGCAGGGGGCGUGGGCCCGGUACAGAAGUUUGUCACCUGGAGACUGAGACGUGACCAGGAGAGGGGCCGGGCCCUGCUGUCUGCCAGGUCUGGGAGUCCCUCCAGCCAGCUGCCUAAUGUGGAUGAGCAGGUUCAGGCCUGGGAGAGCCGGCGGCCCCUCAUUCAGGACCUGGCCCAGAGGCUGCUGACUGAUGACGAGGUGCUGGCUGUCACCCGCCACUGCUCCCGGUAUGUGCACGAGGGAGGCAUAGAGGACCUGGUGAGGCCCCUGCUGGCCAUCCUCGACAGGCCGGAGAAGCUGCUACUGCUGCAGGACAUCAGGAGUGUGGUGGCCCCCACAGACCUGGGCCGCUUCGACAGCAUGGUGAUGCUUGUGGAGCUGGAGGCUUUUGAGGCCCUCAAGAGCAGGGCAGUCCGGCCUCCUGCUUUGAGACCAGCCCGGCAGGACACGCCACCCAAGCGUCACCUUAUCACCCCCGUGCCUGACAGCCGCGGAGGCUUCUACCUGCUGCCGGUGAACGGCUUCCCGGAAGAGGAAGAUAAUGGGGAGCUGAGGGAGCGGCUGGGGGCCCUCAAGGUCUCCCCAAGUGCCUCUGCCCCUCGCCACCCCCAUAAAGGGAUCCCCCCUCUACAAGACGUGCCAGUAGAUGCCUUCACCCCCCUCCGAAUUGCCUGCACACCCCCUCCCCAGCUACCCCCCGUGGCUCCCCGGCCCCUGCGGCCUAACUGGCUGCUGACAGAACCCCUGAGCCGAGAGCACCCUCCGCAGAGCCAGAUCCGGGGCCGGGCUCAGAGCCGUAGCCGCAGCCGUAGCCGCAGCCGCAGCCGCAGCAGCCGGGGUCAAGGCAAGUCUCCAGGUAGACGCUCCCCAUCCCCGGUGCCUACCCCUGCCCCCAGCAUGACCAAUGGGCGCUACCACAAGCCUCGGAAGGCCAGACCCCCUCUGCCACGACCUCUGGAUGGGGAGGCAGCCAAGGUGGGGGCCAAGCAAGGGCCCUCGGAGAGUGGAACUGAGGGGACGGCCAAGGAGGCAGCCAUGAAGAACCCCAGUGGCGAGCUGAAGACAGUGACACUGUCCAAGAUGAAGCAGUCCUUAGGUAUCAGCAUUUCUGGGGGCAUUGAGUCCAAGGUGCAGCCCAUGGUGAAGAUAGAGAAGAUCUUCCCUGGGGGGGCCGCUUUCCUCAGUGGGGCCCUGCAGGCUGGCUUCGAGCUUGUGGCAGUGGACGGAGAGAAUCUAGAGCAGGUGACCCACCAGCGUGCAGUAGACACCAUCCGUCGGGCUUAUCGAAACAAGGCCCGGGAGCCCAUGGAGCUUGUGGUCAGGGUCCCCGGGCCCAGCCCACGGCCCUCACCCUCUGACUCAUCAGCCCUUACUGAUGGGGGCCUUCCUGCUGACCACUUGCCUGCCCACCAACCCCUUGAUGCUGCUCCAGUUCCUGCCCACUGGCUCCCAGAACCUCCCACCAAUCCCCAGACUCCUCCCACUGAUGCCAGGCUCCUCCAGCCAACUCCCAGCCCAGCCCCCUCCCCAGCCCUCCAGACUCCUGAUUCUAAGCCCGCACCCUCCCCACGCAUCCCAUGACCCUCCCCCUAACCUCAGAUUCACCCACUGACUCCAGCAUCCCGUUAUCCCCAGGACCUCUCCUACCAACUUCUUCAGGACUCUCCAGCUCCUGCCCACCCUGCCUCCUCCCAGUGCCACACUGGUGGCUCACAUCUUUCCACUUUCUUCCCUCCUCAGCUGUCAUUAAGGCUCUGCCUUAGUGUCCAAGGACAAGGUGCUAGUGGGCAGCCUGUGUCACCUGCACUCACUGCUCCCCAACCUCCCAAGCCAGGAUAGGGGGUGAGAAAGCCAAGGUCUGGAGCUUGGGAUUGGUGGGCACUUUCUCACAUGCUGUCCCUUAUGAGUCGCCCAAGCCUCCAGGGACACAGACUCUCAGACAGGGCCCUGAAGGGGUCAAUGCAUCCAUUCCUCAACCCCAAGCAGCAUUCUGUGCAAGGAAACGGAUGAAAGGCUUUUCUAGUCCCUGAAAUCCUGAGAGAUCAUUUCACGUUGGGGUCCACUAAGACCUCAGACAUUCUACUGGAUUUGUCCUUCCUCCAUCACCUUUUCUCCCCAAGAGAGCUCUAUGAGGGGGAGGAGAAUAGCCAGCAAAUGGUGGGGGGGGGGGGGUCAAACAAGUUCCUGUACUCUUUAUCCAGCACAUUCACAUUAUUUUUAAACAAAAAAAUUUUUUUUAAUUUUUUCUUUGGGUUUGUACAAGAAAUUUACAGUGUGAAAAAUAUACAAGUGAAAACGAGGCCAUAAACCUGGGUGAAGGGAGAGGCUGCUUGGUCACAAACACAAAUAAACAAGACAUUUCUGAGUUC